AUUCUGCUUUCCAACUGCCUGACUGCUUGUUCGUCUCACUGGUGUGAGCUCCAGCAUCCCCUUUGCUCGAAAUGGACCCCAACUGCUCUUGCGCCACUGGUGGCUCCUGCACGUGCGCCGGCUCCUGCAAGUGCAAAGAGUGCAAAUGCACCUCCUGCAAGAAGAGUGAGUGCGGGGCCAUCUCCAGGAAUCUGGGGCUGUGGCUCAGGUUGGGAGGGAACUCAAGGCUGGCCCUGAGUGCAUCCUUCUGGGGAACUGGGCUUUCUUUGCCCUCAUUGCCCGUGUCAUUCCCUCUCCAGGCUUUCUGCCCUAAAUUCAGAUGGGGCAGGACAGCAUUUUUCUCGUGGGACACAAACCCCAACUGUACCCCCUAUGGUUUCAGAACAGAGCUGUGCCAGACGAAAAAAAGCAUCCUCUGGGUCUGGGUUCUGAGCUCGAGCCAGGCUUGCUAUUAGGGCAGGGAGGUGCCCGGUCAAGUCUACUGCCACCUCUCACUCUCCCCUUCUUCCCCAGGCUGCUGUUCCUGCUGCCCCGUGGGCUGUGCCAAGUGUGCCCAGGGCUGCGUCUGCAAAGGGGCAUCGGAGAAGUGCAGCUGCUGUGCCUGAUGUGGGAACAGCUCUUCUCCCAGAUGUAAAUAGAACAACCUGCACAACCUGGAUUUUUUUAAAAAUACAACACUGAGCCAUUUGCUGCAUUUCUUUUUAUACUAAAUAUGUGACUGACAAUAAAAACAAUUUUGACUUUAA